UCAAACCUGUGAUGGAGGAUUUUGUUUUGUUUUGAAAAAAUACUACAUCAGUGUUAAUGCUCUCAGAGCACUAAAUAUCAGCAAGAAAUGGAUUUCUCCAUUUUACAGACACUCUAUUUUGAAAAAUAUUGAAGAUCUAGUCUUACCUUCAAGAGACCAGUAAAGAGCCAGAAUGGCCCCCUAAGAUGAAAUUACAAUGAUCACCUUGACUACCCAAGGCCUCCUUAGAAGGCCAAGGAACAGAAAGAGAGGGAGAGAGGAAGACCCCAGGAGAAGUGCAGUCCAAGGAGUCCUGCAAAGCAGACUGUGUGGACUGAAAGGCAACUUGCCCUAUUUUGCACCGGACUCAUCUGCAAAACGGGAUGAUGGUAUCUUCCCCAUAGGGCUUCUGUGCUGGAAUACAGAGAGGAACCAAACAGAUAAAAAUCCUUGCCUGCACGGAGCUUACCUUCAGCUAAGGGAGACAGUCAAAAACAAGUCAACACAUCUAAAGAAGCCACUGAUGAAACAGGCUCCCCCUUGGAAAGACCAUCUCACCUUCCAACCUCUCCAUCCUGCAGAGAGGAAAACCCAAGUUUGGCGUUGGCAGUCAGGAUUUAGCCAAAUUUGGGUGCUAUUUCCCUUUUGUGGAGGGACUUUUCAUCACAAUGAGAAGGACGUCUUAGGACUCCAGGACUUUGAGAGAGAAAGUGUCUCUACAAGUCAAAGCAGGAAUAUCAGCCUUCUUACACUAGGACAACUCCAAAAUUGUGUGAUUGGCAAAUUGACAAUCAUCGAUUUGUUGACUGAACACCUGUUAGGUGUAAGGCACGGUGUCAUAUGCUUUCCUUGGGGCUUGCCUUCAAGCAGCUAACAGAAAUAAGAAGAAAACAGGUGAAAAAGACAGUGUGAUAAGGCCAUGGUGGUGGAUUGUGGAUGCCCUGCCCUGUAUCCACUUGGGAGAGAGCCUCUACAACAUGCUGGCAACUUCCCCCUCACUGAUUCAAAUGUUAAUCUCCUUUGGCAACACCCUCACAGACACACCCAGGAUCAAUACGUUGUAUCCUUUGAUCCAAUCAAGUUGCCACUCAGUAUUAACCAUGACACCUUCUAAGCCAUCAUCUCCUCCUAAUCCUCCCAUAACAAUGGGUAUAAGUUAUGAAGGUGGGUUAGAAACUAGUGCCUAUCCCUCACUAAGUUGCCAGAUGGAUUUAACAGCACCUCAAAGUCAACAUGCCCCAAGUCAAAGUCUUCUUUACCCAUGGAAUAAGCUGGCUUGCUACUUCCCUACAUCUCUGAAGGGCUCCACCAUUCCUCUAGCAACCAUGCUCUCAAAGCUCAGAGGGAGGAAAAGGAAAUGGAUCUAAAUGGAAUUCCAGGUCCCACGCUGGAUAUUUUCACACCUUACCUCAUUUAAUACAACAAGCAAGGAGGUAGACAAUAUUGUCUACCUUUGCAAAUGAGGAAACAGAGGCUUAGAGAAGUUAAAUAAUUUGCCUGAGAAUAAAGCUAAAAGUAGCUUUAAAAUACUAGAGCUGGGAUUGCAAGUUUGAUGCAAAGUUUGUGCUCUCUUCAUCCUUCACCAAGAUCUUUCAUUUUCCCUUUAAAUAUCUCUUAUGUCUGCAUUUCCCUUCCAUUCCCAUCACUAGCACUGUCCUCUAAUGCCCCACCCAGUGGGGAAGUCUCCAAUAGGUCCCCCUGCUUAUAACAGCCAAGAGGGUAGCUAUAAACUAGGUCCAAUAACAUGCUUCAUGUGAGGGAACUGAUGGACAGCUGUCUAAUUCAUAACCUCUGGCCUCAACGGAAUUUACAGUUCAGAGUCCAAAAUAGCAAGGAAGUGGUGGGAAGAAGGUGAGAGAAAAGGGUGGGAGGGUGAGAGAGGGGAGGGAGGGGAAUAAGGUGUGGGCAGUAGAGGGAAUCUGUCAGUCUCAUGGUUUGCCCUAGGAAACCUUCUGCUCAGCCCCAGCCUGCUUCUGGGCACUCCUCCUCACCCCUCCUUGCUGUCCAUAUGGGUUCAAUGUGAGUAACCACAAUUGUAGAGUGUGGCCAUCUUCUUCUGACAUGGUCCUAAAUAAACCUAACUGAGUAGCCAGAAGAAUCACUUCUAAGGUAAACAUCUGUAAACAUUGGUUAUAUUUAUUUUCAAUAUUACUGGUUAACAUUGUGGAGCUAUUACUGAUGGGCCAGACUCUGUGCUAGGCACAGACUUUCUAGGGAUUAUUUCAUUUAAUUCUCAUGGCAACCACCAUGCAUUUGCAGAUAGGCAAGUCAGGCUCACAAAAAUGUAUGCAGAGCUUCAGGGUUGUGAUGGGUAGAGCCAAACCCAUCUGCCCAACCCAAGGGCCCGUGCGCUCCAACCCUGCAUCGAACUGCCAACAUAGUACACCUUUUAGAAAAAGAUUCUUGUUGCAAAAGUACCAUAGGCAGUGUGUGUGUAAGGUCAUUGUAAAAGUGUAGAUAAGCAAGAAAGUGUUAUACCACCACUCAGAAGUAACCACUGUUAACAUGUUGGCUUAUCUGCUCUCAGGUGUUUCUGUGCCUGUACAUACUAUUCUUCUUGAAUAAAAACAGGAUUACACAGUG